GUCAUAUAGACCUUUGUGUAAAUCCUGGUUUUGUUAACUUAGUUAUAGGGAAAUGGACAAUUUAAUUUGAUUUUCUGUCUCCUCAUUUAACACUGGAUUUAUUUUUAUUUUUAUUUUUAUUUUUUUAAGACAGAGUCUCUCUCUGUCACCCAGGCUGGAGGGCAGUGGCGUGAUCUCAGCUCACUGCAACUUCUGCCCCCCAGGUUCAAGCAAUUCUUGUGCCUCAGGCGCCUGAGUAGUAGCUGGGGUUACAGGCGUGCACCACCACACCCAGCUAAUUUUUGUAUUUUUAGUAGAGACGGGGUUUCGCUGUGUUGGCCAGGCUGGUCUCAAACUCCUGGCCUCAAGAGAUCCACCCAUCUCGGCCCCACAAAGUACUGGGAUUACAGGUGUGAGUUACCGUGCCCGGCCUAUAACUGGAUAUAAAAAAUCCUUUUACCAGAGUUUGUGAGUCCAGAGUGAGAUAGUGACACUUGGUGGGAGUUAUUCAAUGUACAUUAAUUUAUCUUCUCUUGAUGUAGAAAGUAACAAUCAGCAUGACUUGGUGACUACUAACAAGGAGAGGAAAUUCUAAUCAUUUAAUGUUUCUGAUUUAAUUGAUUUAUUGAUAACUCUCCAUUACUUUUUCAAAUCUCUGAACUAGAAAGGGCUUAUUCAUAGAGUAAAAUGAUUAGAAUCUUUGUUUCAUUGAAAAACAACUAGUUAUAAAAUGGUUUUUUUGUUUGUUUGUUUGUUUGUUUUGAGAUGGAAUUUCGCUUUUGUUGCCCAGGCUGGAGUGCAAUGGUGCAGUCUUGGCCCACGGCAACCUCCGCCUCCCAGGUUCAACUGAUUCUCCUGCCUCAACCUCCCAAGUAGCUGAGAUGACGGCGUGCACCACCAUACCCAGCUAAUUUCUUUCUUUUUUUUUUUUUUUUUCUUUAAGUAGAGAUGGAGUUUCAUCAUGUUGGCCAGGCUGGUCUCAAACUCCUGACCUCAGGUGAUCCACCUACCUUGGCCUCCCAAAGUGCUGGGAUUAUAGGUGUGAGCCACCACACCCGGCCAAAUGGUCUUUUUUUUUUUUUUUUUUGAUACAAGAUCUUGCUGUCAUCCCGGCUGGAGUGCAGUGGUGAAAUCACAGCUCACUGUAGUCUCAACCUCCCAGGCUCAAGUGAUCCUCCUGCCUCAGCCUCUUGUGUAGCCAGGACUACAGGUGCACAGCACCACACUUAGCUAAUUUUUUUUUUUUUUUUUUAAUUUUUAGUAGAGACAAGUUCUCUCUGUGUUGCCCAGGCUGGUCUUGAACUCCUAGGCUCAAAUGAGCUUCCUGCCUUGGCCUCCCAAAGUGCUGGGAUUAUAUGCAUGAGCCAUUGUUCCAGGCCUAAAAUUAUCUUUUUACAACUCAGAUAAAGUAGUCCAUUUGAAAUUCUCCUUGAAAACUUAAAAAACACUUAAGGGAAGUAAACUAGUGUGAAAUAAAGAUCACAAAACACUUUCAGUAGUGUUCAGAAAAAGAAAAAGCAUGUUCCCAAAUAUGAGUUCUCAUGUAAAUCUAAUCUAAAAACUUGGUUCAUAUCAUGGGAAAAUGCCUUUACUUAGAUUGAUAAGAGUGACAAGUUUAGAGCAAAAUAUAAAAUAUGAGGUACUGCUCUAUUUGUAAAGUAAAAAAGAGUCUUAAUAGUGAGAAACGUCUUAUUUUAAUAACUUUUGGUGGGGUGGGUGAGUUGUAAUUUUCACUAGUUUGAGUACACGUAUACAUUUUCCAUGUAAGUUUAACAUGAAGUUUCUACGUUGAGCUGUGGUUCUUCCAUUCCUAAAUCAAUUGUUUUAACAGGUUUCCUGCAAAACGUUUGUAUGUUGUGUAUGUUACACUCUUAAAAUACUAAUUUAUAUGUUUUGUUUAUCAUUUGCAAUUAAGCUUUUAAUAAUAAUGUGAUUGAACAUAAAAGAAUAAUACGCUUAUCCCAAAAAUAAGCACCGUAAAUCAAGAACAUUUAUUCAGCAAUUUUUCAAUGCACACUUUUAUUUAUUUUUUUAAUUUUUAAUUUUUUUCUUAUGAUCUUGUUGCAUACCAGUGUAUGUACUCUUUUAGGCAGUUAUAGAAUAUAGACAAGGCUCAGCCUUUUCUGUCAAGUCUCAUUAGGCCCAUGGGUGAGCAAAAUCUGUAAACUACUUACUGAUCACUUGUAUGUAAAGUAUUAUACUGGUGGAUAGUGACUUUUUUUAUGGAAUCACUGCAGUAUAAUAAGCCAUAUUAAGAGUAUAACACAUAAAUGGUAUAGAAACAGAAAUAAUUAAGAACAUCUGCUGGUUUGUCCACACAAAUCUUGUACACAAAUGUGCAUAGCGGCUUUAUUCGUAAUAGCCCAACUGCAAACAACUCAAGUCUAUCAACAAUUAAAUGAUAAACAGAUUGUGUUACAUCCAUGCAAUGAAAUAGUAUUCAGCAAUAAAAAGAACAAAAAUCCUUACGCUCAACAGCAUGGAUGAAUCUCAGAAUAAUUAUGUCCAUGAAAGAAGCCAGAAAAAAAGAGUACAUACUAUAUAAUCCCAUUUAUAUAAAAUUCUAGAAAAUGGAGCUACUAAAGUGUAAAGCACAUUGAUAAUUCCUGGCAAGGACAGGAAGGUGAGACUGCAAAGAAACUUACAGAAAUUGUGGCAGUAUUCCUUAUCUUGAUUGUGGUGGUGAUAUAUAUGUUAUAACUCAUCAAAUUGUCCACUAUGCAGUUUAUUGUACAUGAAUUAUAUCAGGAAAGCAUUCAUAAAGUGAUUUUUAAAGAACCUAUGCUGGAAGUACAGAUGUGAUUGAUUCCAUAAAUAUAUUGGAAUAAUCCUUGGAGAGAUUAGAGUGUAUACCCUGGUAAACCUAAAUUGAUAUGCUAUCAAACACAGGAUCAGUGAGUCCCAACAGAACUACCACCAGAGUUCAGUGUAGAGAAAGACAGCUUGGUUUAAUGAUAAAAUGAGGAUAGGAUUUAAUUAAAGUCAGAGGCUCUGAAUUUGAAUCCCUGUUAGGCCAUAUUUUCUCUAAUCUUUAUUUUUCUCAUCUUUAGUUUCAUUAAGAUUUUAAGAUCCAAAGAAUAUAUUUGAAAGUACAUCUGAAAGUGACAUAAAAAUGGAAGGCUGGCCGGGCGCGGUGGCUCACACCUGUAAUCCCAGCACUUUGGGAGGCCGAGGUGGGCGGAUCCCAAGGUCAGGAGCUCGAGACCAGCCUGGCCAACAUAGUGAAACCCUGUCUCUACUAAAAAUACAAAAAUUAGCUGGGUAUGGUGGCACGCGCCUAUAAUCCCAGCUACUCAGGAAGCUGAGGCACGAGAAUUGCUUGAAUCCGGGAGGCAGAGGUUCAAGCAAUUCAAGAGCCAAGAUUGCACCACUGCACUCCAGCCUGGGCAACAGAAUGAGACUCCGUCUCAAAAAAAAAAACAACAAAGGCUUUCCUGACAUUUAGCUUAGAAGGGAAAACAAAAUAAAGUAGAAUUUGACCUGUGGAGAUCAGUGAGGAGGGAAUUCCAAAAAGGGACCAGAGCUGGGAGAGUGGGAAUAUGUAUGAUACAUAUGGAAAAUGAUGAGUCAAAAGCAGUUUAGGGCAAAGAGUUCAUUUUGCAGAGCAGGGAGGGAGAGAUAGCAGCCUAAAGUAUCUAAAAGCAUAAUAGAGAGAUUAUAAAAUAGCGAGAAAGUUUACCAUCAGGAUAUAAGUUGCUGUUACUAGCCCUGUAAGCUUAGCCAAGUCAUUUAAUUCUCUGAGCCUCAAUUUCCCCAUCAAUGUAAUGGGAGAUAAUAAUAGUUCUGCCAGAUCUCAAGGAUUUUAUGUAUUUAAAUCAGUCCAUGUCAGAUGUGAUAGAGUGUAGGAUAGUACUGAAAAGUACCAAGUACUGUUGAUAGUUCAGCGUGAUUAUCAAGCUGUGGGCUAAUAAGUGUCUGGACUCAGAUAAUUGUAUUUUAGAGACAGUUUAAAUAACAGUAAAGAUUAAUAUAAGGCCGGUGAGACUGAAGGCAAGGAAAUCAAUCAGGAUGCUGUUUCAGUAGUCCAAGGCAGAGGCAGAGGCAGUGGCAGUGGAGAAAGGAAGGGAUGGAUUUGAGAUAGGUCUUGGUGACCAGGUCUGUGUUAGGAGGAAAAGGGGAAGAGAAAUUGUAUUAGUUUUCUGUGGCUGUUGUAAUUAAUUAUCACAAAUUAGAUGGCUUAAAACAACGAAGUAAUUUCCUCACAGAAGCUUGAAAUAAUCAUAACUGGGUUGAGAUCAAGAUGUUGGCAAGUGCUCCUUCCCUCCGAAGGAUCUAGGAGAGAAACCAUUCCUUGCCUCUUGCAGCUUAUGUGGGCUGCAGGCAUAUUCAUCUUGUGACUAUAUCAUUCAUCACUGGUCUUCACGUUGCUACACCACCUCCUCUUCCCCACUUUUCACCUUCUCCUGUGUGUGCCAAGUCUACAUCUGCCUUCCUUGUAUAAGGAGACUUGUGACUGUAUUUAGGGCCCACCUGGGUAAUCUGGGAUAAUCUCCCCAUUCCAAGAUAUUUCAUCACAUCUGCAAAGCCAUAAAGGUAUCAUUCACAAAUUCAAGGGAUUAGAACAUGGACAUUUGGGGGUUUUAGCUUUUUGGAGCUGGUCCUGUCAUUGACCAGAGUACUUGAAAAAGAAGAAUGCAUUUUUGAGAGAUGAUAAUGAAUUCACUUGGGAUCUGCUGAAGUACCUAUGGGCCAUGUGUAUGAGGGUAUUCAAUUUAUGUUAUCAGAAAACCUCGAAUCAGGUGGCUUAAACAAUACGGACAUUUAUUUAAAACAAAAAACAGCCUCAGAGUUGGUUAAAUUAGCAAUUCAGUGACAUCCUUGAGGACAUACGUUCUUGCUUUGCCAUCCUUAGGCUGGCUCUCCUAUGGUAACAAAACGAUCCCCACAAUUCUAGGCCUUCAAUACAGAUAUGCAAAUUUAGUUGGCUUGUUUUGUGUGCCCCACCCCCACCUUUUUUUUUUUAAAGUCUGCAAGGAAACCUAACUUCUGAAGCUACCCAUUAGCUUCUAUUUUUCUUGGCCAGAUAAACAUUCUCUUGACCACCGUCUUUUACCUAAAUCUUUUUUUUUUUUUUUUUGAGGCAGAGUCUUGCUCUAUUGCCCUGGAGCUGGAAGUGCAGUGGGAUCUCGGCUCACUGCAACCUCCACCUCCGAGUUCAAGCAAUUCUCCUGCCUCAGCCUCUUGAGUAGCUGGGAUUACAGGCAUGCGCCACUGUGCCUGACGAAUUUUUGUAUUUUUAGUAGAGACGGGGUUUCACCAUGUUGGCCAGGCUAGUCUUGAACUCCUGACCUCAGGUGACCCACAUUCCUCAGCCUCCCAGAGUGCUGGGAUUACAGGCGUGAGCCACCGCACCCAGCCACCUAAAUUUUUUAUAUCUACGUUGCAGAUUUGUUCAGGUAAGGGACCCCUGCCUCAAAUACACAAACAUUACACCCAUCCAUCUUCAGUGACAAAUGGCAAAACAGACCUCUUGAGCACUUCCCACAUCACAUUGUUUUACUACUUUUUGCUAUGCAGAUUUGGUAGAAUCUUGCAGAUGUGGAACUGUCUUUCUGUGGUUUAUUUAAACAGCAGUCCAUUCACCUUGCUUAGUCUUGUUUUAAGUUCUUGUCUACAAAUUCCUAACCAUGUCCUCAUUUUCUUUUUCUUUUUUUUUUUUUUUAAGACGGAGUCUCGCUCUGUCACCCACGCUGGAGUGCAGUGGUGUGAUCUCAGCUCACUGCAACCUCCGCCUCCCGGGUUCAAGCGAUUCUCGUGCCUCUGCCUCCCAAGUAGCUGGGAUUACAGGACAUUUCUGAUUUAUUUGCAUCCUUGAAGAGCAUCUGUAGAAGAGGAAGUAAAAGAUGGGUGUGAAAACAUUUACUCAUAGCUCCUCUUCCCACAGCCAGGAAAUGCUUGGAAAGCUAAAUAUGCUGCGAAAUGAUGGACAUUUUUGUGAUAUCACUAUUCGUGUCCAGGACAAAAUCUUCCGGGCACAUAAGGUGGUACUAGCAGCUUGCAGUGAUUUCUUUCGCACCAAACUUGUAGGCCAAGCCGAGGAUGAGAACAAGAAUGUGUUGGAUCUGCAUCAUGUUACAGUGACUGGCUUUAUACCUCUUUUAGAAUAUGCUUACACAGCCACUCUAUCAAUUAACACAGAAAAUAUUAUUGAUGUUCUAGCAGCAGCCAGCUAUAUGCAAAUGUUCAGUGUUGCCAGCACCUGCUCAGAGUUCAUGAAAUCAAGCAUUUUAUGGAAUACACCCAACAGCCAACCUGAAAAGGGUCUAGAUGCUGGACAAGAAAAUAAUUCUAACUGCAAUUUUACUUCUCGAGAUGGGAGCAUUUCUCCCGUGUCCUCAGAGUGCAGUGUGGUAGAAAGAACCAUUCCUGUCUGCCGAGAAUCCCGGAGAAAGCGCAAAAGCUACAUUGUUAUGUCUCCUGAAAGUCCUGUAAAGUGUGGCACACAAACAAGCUCACCCCAGGUAUUGAAUUCUUCAGCUUCCUACUCAGAAAAUAGAAACCAACCAGUUGACUCUUCCUUAGCUUUUCCUUGGACUUUUCCUUUUGGAAUUGAUCGAAGGAUUCAGCCUGAGAAAGUUAAGCAAGCAGAAAAUACCCGGACUUUAGAAUUACCUGGCCCAUCUGAGACCGGUAGAAGAAUGGCUGAUUAUGUGACUUGUGAGAGCACAAAAACUACCUUGCCUUUAGGUACCGAAGAAGAUGUCCGGGUCAAAGUAGAAAGAUUAAGUGAUGAGGAGGUCCAUGAGGAAGUGUCCCAGCCUGUCAGUGCAUCUCAGAGUUCGCUGAGUGAUCAGCAGACAGUUCCAGGAAGUGAACAAGUCCAAGAGGACCUUCUGAUUAGUCCACAGUCUUCCUCUAUAGGCUCAGUAGAUGAAGGCGUUUCUGAGGGCUUGCCUACACUUCAAAGCACGUCUAGCACUAAUGCUCCUCCGGAUGAUGAUGAUCGAUUGGAAAAUGUUCAGUAUCCCUACCAACUCUACAUUGCUCCUUCCACCAGCAGUACAGAGCGACCAAGUCCAAAUGGUCCCGACAGACCUUUUCAGUGUCCAACCUGCGGGGUGCGAUUCACCCGUAUUCAGAACCUAAAGCAGCACAUGCUCAUCCACUCAGGAAUUAAACCAUUUCAGUGUGACCGCUGUGGGAAAAAGUUCACCAGGGCUUACUCGCUAAAGAUGCAUCGCCUAAAGCAUGAAGGUAAACGCUGUUUCCGGUGCCAGAUAUGUAGUGCCACUUUCACUUCCUUCGGGGAAUAUAAACACCACAUGAGGGUUUCCCGGCACAUUAUCCGCAAGCCUCGGAUUUACGAGUGCAAAACAUGUGGCGCCAUGUUCACCAACUCUGGAAAUUUAAUCGUGCACCUGAGGAGUCUGAACCAUGAAGCAUCAGAGCUAGCAAACUACUUCCAGAGCAGUGAUUUCCUAGUACCGGACUACUUAAACCAGGAACAAGAAGAGACCCUUGUUCAAUAUGAUCUUGGAGAACACGGUUUUGAAAGCAACUCCUCUGUUCAAAUGCCUGUCAUUUCACAGGUCUCCUCAACCCAGAAUUGUGAAAGCACUUUUCCCUUGGGGUCUCUUGGUGGGCUGGCAGAAAAAGAGGAAGAAGUGCCAGAGCAGCCAAAGAGCAGUGCUUGUGCUGAGGCAACCAGAGAUGACCCCCCAAAAUCAGAGCUGUCUUCUAUAACUAUUGAGUAGUUUUGUGAUUUGGCUUCAGUUUUGUUUUUUGGAAAGUGCCUGUGCUUGGUCUUGUACAUUUAAAUUUAAUUUAAUUUUUUAAACAAAAAAAGCCGGGUGGGAGGGAGGGGGAGAUUGGGAAAGAAUUUCCCUUUUUACUUUCUGAGCCCUGAAACUGAUUUUAUUUUUCCUAACUGAGAGAUUGCUUCUGUAAGUACACAAUAACAUGAUGUUGAAACAGAAACUAUGAGACUUAAGGAGAACUGGUUGACUUAAAACAUAUACCAGUUCCUUCUUCCAUUGUUAAAAGUAGGCUAACAACAGAUCAUUAGCUAGAGAGGAAAUCAGAUGAUUAUUGACCUUCUUGAGACAAGAGGGUACAUGAGAAACUAAUUACUAAACAGCUUGACAAAUGGCCUGAGUAGAUACUUACUGCUGUACACAGGAUGUUGUAUAAUAUUUUGUAAAGCCUGUUGUUUUUGGAAGUAUUUAUGGUAAGCUUUCUUAAAAAUUAUUAUGGUAAAUACUUCUGAAAUCCGGCGUACUUUUCUUUAAGCUUUGUCAUUUCUGUUAUGAUUUUUCAUGGUGAAAUUUUGGUACUGAGAUGGGCAUUCUCUGUACCUUUAUAGUACCACUCCAAAGGCAAGGAACCAUGAUUGACAACAGUCAAGCUGUGGAUGAAAUGACCAGGAACGGAGAAUGAAGUAUGUAAAUCCCAGCUUCAUAGGAACUCUUCUCAUACUGCUUUUCAGAUUAAAAUUGCUGUUUACCUGGUCUCCGAAUGUAAUGCCUGACUGUGUCAUUGCCCGGAUCAGUUUUCCCCCUGCCCCAUCAAUAUGUUCUCUUGCAUAUAUUGGCGUGCUGCCAUAUAAAGUAAAAAUACUGGAGAUAUUCUAUAUUUUAUAUAUAGGUUUAUGUGUUGUUGGGGAUGUUUUCAUUGUGCUCUUUUGGACAUAAUAAAUAAUUCUCUAUUGAGGCUACAUUCUUUUUUUUUUUCUUUUUUUUUAAAAGAAUGGCAUCUCACUCUGUUGCCCAGGCUGGAGUAUAGUGGCUAAGUCAUAGCUCACUGCAGCUUCGAACUCCUGGGCUCAGGCCAUUCUCCUGCCUCAGCCUCUUGAGUAUCUAGGAUUAUAGGCAUGCUCCACCACACCUGGUUAACUUCAUUUUUAUUUUUUGUAGAGAUGAGGUCUCACUAUGGUGCCCAGGCUGGUCUUGAACUCCUAGACCAAGUGAUCCUCCUCCUUUGGCCUCCCAGACUGCUGGGAUCACUGCACCGGCCAAGGCUGCAUUCUUAACCCAACUAGAUUGUUUACUGAAUCCCAUAUGACAGCGAUACAUUGUCCUUACAUAUUUAUUUUUAGACAUUGCAAAGUUAUUAAAAACAGUUAACUAUAGUUUUUACACAACGUAGGCAACAAUGAAGAGUAUAGACUGUAAGAUUUUCAUCUAUGACUCAUAAAUCUGGGAGAAAAAAAUUAUUAAGACUAAUGAGAAACUGAAAACCUUAAACUAAUGAAUAUUAUUUCUGCUGCUAAAAAUAUGAAACUUUCUGGUCUGUAGUUGAAAUUUGUAUGAUCCUCUAGACUUGGGUAUACUUUUCAUCUGGUGCCAUUAAAGCAUCUCUAAUAUUGAUCCUAAAUAUUUGUAAGUCCAUGAGCAGUGAACUUUGGAAUAAGUUUCUGUGUAGAUACCCAAAGUUUAAUAAUUAUGAGAGCACCUGAUUUGAUAGACAGAAAAUACAGUUCUUUAGUCAAAACACAAGAUCUGAAUUUUGUUCAGGUGCUAGACCAUACUAAAUGUAUAUAUUUUUAAUUAUAGUGAUUUGUUUCAUUUUUUUAGAUUGGCUAAUUCUGUAAUUUUUUCCCCAAAAACAUGUGAAGAAAGGAAAAGUAAAUUAAAUUCCUUAGAACUGUUUUAGGUUAAGAUUCUCUGUGUCUGCCCAUAUUCUGCAGUCCUUAACUUGUUUUCAACUCUUUACCUCACUCAUGAACUUGUUUUUACCCAUUUGCUGCCAAACAUAGGUGUGUUCCCUUCAGGAGAAUCAGCAUAUACAGGUUAUGAUAGGCUCCCACCAUUUAUGCUUCUUCACUGAUAGGGUUGCAUUACUUUCUGCAGCAGACUAUAAUACUUCAUAUAGUACUGCUGUGUCUCAACUGGAAAGGUCAGGAAUUUUAAUGUUACGUUGUGGUCUUUGAAAACUGUUAGGCCUAGCAAUAGAUAAAUCUCAAAAUUAAUUUUAAAAUCUGUAUUGACAAGAAUAGGUAAAAUUAUGACCAGGAAUCAUUGUUACCCUUAGUUCCAAGAGGUGGUUUUUGAAAGAGCAAGAGGAAAGAAAAAAGAAAAGAAGGAAAGAAGAAUAAAGAAGAGAAACGUGUAAGAAUGGUUUGCAGAUUGAUUGGUUAAAAGUGUUUUUAGCACAUCCCCAACCCUGAAAACUUCGCAUUAAGAGCCAAGCACAAUGUUGGUAGCUCCAAGAUAUUCUGACUGUGUUCUCAGAAUGAGGGAUUACCCAUCACUGGGUAUUCCUUCCCAAGUAGAAACUUUAGAUUUUCACUGGUAAUACACAUUGCCAAGUUUUAUGGGAAAUCUGAAUAUACUGUGAAAAUGCAUAUCUGGUUAGUUGUCUGCUGCCCAGAUCUUAUCAAUACCAGUAACUAACCAGUAUUUAACAUAAAAUGAUACAAAUAAAGGCCUUUUUCUAUUUCAGUGAGGGUACAUUUUUCUUGAUAUAUAUGUACUUUAAGGAUAUUGGAUCUGUUUAUGGAUCUGUUUUAGGAAACAGAUUUGCAAGGGAUAAUUGUAUAUAUAGUAGUAUUUAGGUUUAUUUCAAAUUCAUCUUAGGGAUGCCUAGAUGCAUAAUUUUUACCAGGACAUAUUGAAAAUAUUGCAAAGAGAUAGCCAGUUAUAUUAUCCCAUUCAUUAGAAAUUACCAGUGUAACUAAACAUAAAUAUUCCAGUUUAGAGUGCUUAAACGUAGCUAUCUUUCUUAAGGCCAGGAGGGUAACUUUGUGGUAUCUAAAGGGCUUAAAUUUCAGAAUGCAGAAUAAAUUGCCUUUUUAAAACCAAGCAUUUUGUACAAGCUUUUAUUUUCAGUUUUUUAACUACCAAAUAGGUGUGAUGUACUUUAGAAGUAAACAAAGAUGUUCACCCAUGAUAAUGGAUGUUAAAGCUCCUGCAGUUGUUCUUUUCGUGUUUAAAGGGUAUAUUCUAAUAGUGGAAGCAUCAAACAUGUCAGUGAUUUCAUCUCAUUCAGAAAUAAAGAGAUUAAUAUUGGUCUUUAUUUUUUGGCAUUUUAAGUUUUAUAUAAAUGGAUGCAGAUGGAGAUUAUCACCCACAAAUAUAUUUAAAUGGAUUUUUCUUAAUUUGAAUUUCAAGUAAUCUUUUUAUUUCAAGUAAUUAGUUACGCAUUUAGUUACAUUGCCAGUUUUUUUUUUUUAUCAAUUUCAGUAAGACAAAAUAUACUAAAAUGUUUAAAUAGCCUCAUUCAAUCUUACAUUUUGACAUUUCAGCAAUCAUUCUGGCUUACAGUAAUUAGAUCCCCUGUUACGACACAUGCCCUUUGUUCUUAAUAACUAGCAAAAAAAAAAAAAAAAAAAAACUUUCAUCUUGUUAAAAUACUUUGCCAAAUGAAAUAGACUAGUCAAUACAUCUGAUGUCCAUAAUUAUUGGUAACUCAGUUACCUUCUAACUAAUAGGCUGGUUCAGGAGACUCUCCCAGUUUAUAAAUGGUUCUCUUGGGAGCCUUUGGAAGCUGUAUUAAAUCUUUCAGUCUUUUAUUUCUAAUUUUUUCUCUUAAUCUAAAUAGAGGCCAGUUAUCUAUUUUAUCAGCUUUUAUUCUUGAAGAUUCUCAGAUUAUGUUUUAGUCCCUUUUAGCUUUAAUAGUCCUUGAAAAAUACAUUACUGUAUAAUGUGGCAAUUCUGUAACAGAGACUUAUUACUUGAAUGAAUAAUCCUAAAAUUUUAAUAUUUUAGCUGAAGUUUGAGAUUUGUGGAAUGAACAAAAGAAUUAGAAACUUUCAUAUGUUACUUUGUUUCAGUCAUCUGCAAAGUAUGAAGCUGUAAUUCUGAAAUACACAUCCAAGUGAAUGAGAAUUAAAAAUUUUCUAAAUAUUAAUACUAACUGGGAAAAAAAAACUAGUGUGAAGUUUACAGUUAGAAGAAACAGACCCAAAGUUGCCAGAAGGUAAUAAAUAAAUGUAGUUUUCACUGUAAGUAAGUUAUUGACGUAAGAUGCUUUAUUUGUAAUAUAUUUAGAUUUUGAAAGUUAUUGAGAGAUGAAUGUAUAAAAGCUAAAUUUUCUUUUCUGAAGCAGUGAAACAAAAUUGGGGUAACAAGGAAGCUCUGUUGUGGCAAACAUGUCUAUGAGGAAUAUUAAAACUAAGCAUACUCCCACAGGCUUUAAACUCAAACUAUGAACAUUUAAAUUAAGUUGUUCCUUAUUUUGCCUAUACCCAUUUUUAUCUUUCAUUGUCGUUUUUGCUUGACAGUAUGGUGACAGAGUAUUUUUAUUUGGAAAGUCCUCAGCAAGAUGAAUUAGCCAAAAGCAAUAAUGGUUCAGAUUAAACAAUAAAGUGGAAUUGAUUCAAUCCCAGGCUCAACUAAGAACAGUCGCUCUCUGGAUGUUUCAUUUUAGACGAUAGAUAAGUUGAGAUGUUGUAAUAUUUAUGGGGGGUUAAGCCUGUGUCAGUUAUGGGAUGAAGACUUGUAGUACCAGUACCAUCAGUGGUCAUACUUUUUUUUAACUUUUUACUAAACUAAUACAGUUAGACAUUUCCACUCUAUCGUGAUUAUAUUUUUAUGAUGGGAAAAUAAAAACACUUCCAUGUUUUUAUAAAUAGUCUCUGCAAAGAUUUCAGAUGUUAUUGGUAUCUCGGUUUGGCAGUAUCUGAAAAAUUGAGAUUGUCUUUGAAAUGUUUGUGCUACUUUUACUUAAGUAAACCCCCACUGUGCAAGACCCAGGCCGGCUUCAGCUAAUACCAAGGUUUCUGUGUGCAUAAUAGUUUACAGAGAACUUAAGAGUAAGGACUGCGGAUUAAAAACAAAACUUUUUUUAACUUUAAAAUUUUUAGUUUUUGUUCAAAGUACCUGGUUUAUAAAGUCAAAUUCUUUUAUUAGUUCCUUUCUCGUUUAAAUUGACUGAUGUUGCUGAUGAAGCUUAAAGUCCCAGGCACGGUUGUGGCGAUAUACUGAUAAAAUUGGUGCCUAGUGGUGGGAGGAGCUCCAGUGUCAGGACUUUUAUUAAAAGGCCCUUGUUUUCCCAAAUGCCAAUCUAGCCACAUUUAGAUUUCAUUAUUCAAUAAAACAGAUGAAAAAUCAUCCCAUAAAUGAAUGUUGAGGUUACCAAAGUACAUCACCUGCUGAGGAAGGAUAAAUCUUCCUGCUUUAAGGGAGCCCUGUCAUCUCUCCUCUUAAUGCACGUUUCCCUUGGUAUUAGUGGAAGCUGUGUUCAAGAUGGGAAGCCUUUCCUGCAGUUCUUAGAAACACCUGCUUUCUAAGGAGAGCCUUUUCUAGGAUUAGCUUAUGUGUGUUUUCUCUAGGCGAUUUUUUAUUUCAGUUACCAAUUUAAUUUUCAAGUUGACAGAUGCUGUGUAAAGUCUCUCAUAAUGAGAGUAGUCCAUUAAAUUGUUGAAAGUUGCACUGCUUUUCAUCUUUCAGGUACCUGAAAUGAGUGACAUCAGGUAUUUGGAAGGAGUAAGAUCAUAAACUGUAUUCAUUUUCUUCCUUGUACAAAGUGAUGACUUCUAAUGCUUAUAUCUCAAGGUAUUUUUUAAAAAAGCAACGGUCCCUAAUAGAGUAAAAUUUGGUUUUGGUCCAAGUUCCCAAUAAUGUAUUUAAUGUUUCUGUUGUUUACUGGUGCCUCCCGUUGCAUCAGGUAGAGAUUGCCUGCCUCUUUGUAGGGCAGCCUUGUGGCACCUUAUGUCCAACUUGGAGGAUAGUAUAUGGCUUCUUUGUGCCUCUACUAUCUUUUCAAAAGCCAUUUUAUAAAAAUCCUAGGUAGCCUAUUUUAAUAUUUAAAUAUAUAUAUUUGUGAAAGAACUUUUAGAACAGACCUUUUCUUUUUACUUUAAAAUUCCUGUAUUUCCAUUUUUAAGAGUAAAUUUAAUCUCCAGGAUUUAGAAGUGUCUUUCCAGAGAAGCAUAAUGAGAAAGUCAGACUGAGGUAAUAAGACCAGAAUUAAGUGAUAGAAGAAACUGUUGUUUGGUUAAAGGACACAGAUUUGAAGGAAAAAAAUUUUGAUGUAACAAUUUUUUAAAUAAAAUUUUGUUUUUCUGUAAUGUCAUAUUUGCUGCUACAGUAGCUCAAUAUUUUACAGGGCUAACAUAAAGCUGGCUCCAUUUAAAAACUGGAGUACUUCCUAGUGCAGCCAGCCUAGGCGGAAACUGUACACCAUGGUCUUCCAGAUGGGUGACUGAUGGCUUUGGGUAGCUGAUGCAUGCUUUAAUAUUUGCCUAUAGCCCGGCAGCAAGGAAGUCGGGGCGGGGGGACUUUUUUACCCUGCCAGUUAUAGCAUUGUGAUUCUUUCUGGGCACUGGCAUUUUGUGAAACUCUCAAGGGAAGGUGAUGCAGGGGAGAAAAUGUGAAUUAAAUUACAUAGAUGGGUGUUUUUAUGUCUUCUACCCCUUUCCUAGAAUUAGUACAACUCUUAACUGUGCCAGUCCCCAGUUCACCAGCUUUGUAUCCAGUCGUCAUCUCAUUCAAGUAUGGCUUUACUUGGUGACACUGGCCAUAGCUAAGUUAACUUGGCAUGUUUGACUUUUGACAAUAACAAAAAUGGUUUUGGAUUUUGUUUUAUUUCCAAAAAAUGUAUACAAUAUCAGAACUUCACAUUUUAUAUACUAGUAUCUGGCUAUUAGUAUUUUACAGGAACCAUAGUUCUUGGUGACUACAUAUAUAUAUAUAUUUUUGUGACCUUUUUUGUAAACUAAGUGCCGUUUCAACGUUACAAUCAUUUUUAGGGUUAUUGUAAUCAAUGUGAAUAUCAUGUUUUUUCAAAUCUGUUCUGAGCCUAUAGUGUUUGCUUUGUGAACAUGUGUAUUGUAUAUAUUCUGUAUAGUUAUAUUGUACUGAAAUUAGCUUGUUUGAUAUAAGGAAAAUAUGUAUUGAGUACCUUUUUGCUAGCCUGAUUGUUUAAUCUUUUUAAAAAAGGUUUAAACUUUUUUUAAAAAAAAAAUCUUUAAACUGGCCUUUAUUACAUGGUCACACAUAAAGUUGCAGUUAGGAAAGGGAUGGGCAGGGAAAAACUAGUUUUGAGUGUCUUUAGAUAGAAACAUGAGACUAAGGUUUGAUUUUGUUUUCGUUUUCUCAUUAAAAUAUCUUAUGCUUUAUGGAAUAAAA